CUAGACGCCGUACGUGCCAGAUGGUGUUACCUGGAGCUUAAAAAGCUGCACGCAAGUGUUAAACUUCUGUAGGAGGAAUACUGUUGGCGUUCAAAAGCAUUGCUGUUUCAGUUAAGUAGUUCCUUAAUUACUUACAAUGUAGUAAGGCUACAUUGAAGGAAGAUAUAAAUUUCAGUCAAGACUACGACUGAGCAAAGACAAUGGCCAAGAACAAAUUAAGAGGGCCGAAGUCCAGGAAUGUAUUUCACAUAGCCAGCCAAAAAAACUUUAAGGCUAAAAACAAAGCAAAACCAGUUACCACUAAUCUUAAGAAGAUAAACAUUAUGAAUGAGGAAAAAGUUAACAGAGUAAAUAAAGCUUUUGUAAAUGUACAAAAGGAACUUGCACAUUUCGCAAAAAGCAUUUCACUUGAACCUCUGCAGAAAGAACUGAUUCCUCAGCAGCGUCAUGAAAGCAAACCAGUUAAUGUUGAUGAAGCUACAAGAUUAAUGGCUCUGUUGUAAUAUACUGGUGAUGCAUCUAAUUCUCCACAAAGACCAAUAAAUUGAAUGUUUUAUACAAUUUUAUUUUUAAAAAUCUUGUUAAUGUACAGGCAUUGGCACAUUUUAAAAACAAACUACAUAAACAGAUCUUUCCUAUAACCUAGGAAAGUGGAAUGUCAGAAGUCAACAAAAUGUGAUAAACUUAAAGUGCUAAAACAGAAGGCACUUCACAAAAUCUGUUCACUGAAACAGUUAUAUAUCCUCGUUUACAUCCUUCACUUUACAAGUGGCAGUGAACGUCUGUUUGGAUAGAAGGACAUACAGAAAUACAGGCAGUUUAGUGGCAGUAAAAAUAUAAGACAAGUAAUGAGUCCUUGGCCAACUUGUUUUUGAUGACCUGUAGUGUCCUUUAACUUUCCUCCUUAAGAAGAAAAAACAGAAGGAUUCACAAUUAGAAGAAAAGUUGAAAUCCAGAAUAUAGUUACUUUUGGGAGUGGGGACGUUUGUGGAUAUUAAAUCACUUAUCCCCUAAA